GGGAAGCUAGCUAGGGAGCUGGGGUGAGACGUGCUGUGCUCACCCUAACCACACUCUGACAAGGAAAGCUGGCGAAGUCUCUUAUCUUACAGUUGAAAGAUCAGGCCCUGGAGGCCUAUAUAACCCAUAUGAGAUCUCUUUCUAGGGUUCCCAGGAGCCGAGGUGCCCAUCUGAGCCUGAUCUUCCUGAAAUCUUUGGGAAGCUCACCUUCCAAGACUCCCCAUGAUGAGCAGUAUUGAUUUUUCUGGGUCCCCACAUUGCUUAGGGAAAUAGGUUCCUCCACCUCCCAUUGGCCUUUUUGUGCUUACCCUGAGAAGCUGUGUCAGGCCACUGUGUCAGGUGUCAGGCUUAGCCCAGAGAGAGUGAGGUGGAGGAGGCGGAGGGUGUAACCCAGCCAGGUCCUCUUCACAUAAGCUAUCAGACAAGCUCCUCAGGGCAGCAGCUCCUCAAGGCCCCAGGAACAUGGCUGUCCCCUGGCUAGUGCUACUCUUGGCAUUGCCCAUCUUUUUCCUGGGGGUCUUUGUCUGGGCUGUCUUUGAGCACUUCCUCACCACGGAUAUCCCUGCUACCUUGCAGCAUCCUGCCAAGUUGAGAUUCCUGCAUUGCAUAUUCCUCUACCUGGUCACUUUGGGGAAUAUAUUUGAGAAGCUGGGAAUUUGCUCCAUGCCCAAAUUUAUUCGUUUUUUACAUGAUAGCGUGAGAAUUAAAAAGGACCCUGAACUUGUGGUGACCGACCUGCGUUUUGGGACGAUACCCGUGAGGCUGUUCCAGCCGAAGGCAGCAUCCUCCAGACCCCGGCGAGGCAUCAUCUUCUACCAUGGAGGGGCCACAGUAUUUGGGAGCCUGGAUUGUUACCAUGGCCUGUGCAAUUAUCUGGCCCGGGAGACUGAAUCUGUACUUCUGAUGAUUGGGUACCGCAAGCUUCCUGACCACCAUUCCCCUGCCCUUUUCCAAGACUGCAUGAAUGCCUCCAUUCACUUCCUGAAGGCCCUGGAAACCUAUGGGGUGGACCCCUCCAGGGUUGUGGUCUGUGGAGAAAGCGUCGGAGGUGCAGCGGUGGCCGCCAUCACCCAGGCCUUGGUGGGCAGAUCAGAUCUUCCCCGGAUCCGGGCUCAGGUUCUGAUUUAUCCAGUUGUCCAGGCAUUCUGUUUGCAGUUGCCAUCCUUUCAGCAGAACCAAAAUGUCCCAUUACUUUCCCGGAAGUUCAUGGUGACUUCUCUGUGUAACUAUCUGGCCAUUGACCUCUCCUGGCGUGACGCCAUCUUGAACGGCACUUGUGUACCCCCAGACGUCUGGAGGAAGUACGAGAAGUGGCUCAGCCCUGACAACAUCCCCAAGAAAUUUAAGAACAGAGGCUACCAACCCUGGUCUCCCGGCCCUUUUAAUGAAGCUGCCUAUCUAGAAGCCAAACAUAUGCUGGAUGUAGAAAAUUCACCCCUGAUAGCAGAUGAUGAGGUCAUCGCUCAGCUUCCUGAGGCCUUCCUGGUGAGCUGUGAGAAUGACAUACUCCGUGAUGACAGCUUGCUCUAUAAGAAGCGCUUGGAGGACCAGGGGGUCCGCGUGACAUGGUACCACCUGUAUGAUGGUUUUCACGGAUCCAUUAUCUUUUUUGAUAAGAAGGCUCUCUCUUUCCCAUGUUCCCUGAAGAUUGUGAAUGCUGUAGUCAGUUAUAUAAAGGGCAUAUGAUAGUAACCCUGGGGCCCCGAGGAGGAAGGGGCAAGUAUGGACUCUACCAGAAACCGGGUGCUUUAGUGAGUUCUAUUUUAUUGACUAAAGAGGUGCUACAUCAAUGCUUGGGGCAGCUGGGAAGGGUGAGAAGUAAGCUAACAGUCUUGCUUAGUAUUCAAGAAAAUCCAAACUGUGUCUGUUUCCUUCCAGCACUAACAAUGUCCAUUGCUGGAUCUAGCGACAUUCUCUAACAUUCCCAUUUAGGUGAAAUAAAUAUCAAAAGGAGAAAAAAAUGCCUUUAAAAAUUUCUCAAAGCCCCAACAUAUAAGAUCUGUGCAGAAUAAAUGCCAACAACUGGU